GCGAAGAAAUGCGGGCGGAAGGCGCGCUGAGGGCGGCUGUAGUUUUCCGAGACCAACUUUCCCGACAGCACCGUGCGCCUCCCGCCUACGGAGAACUACAUGCCCCAGCCUGCCCCGCGAAGGGAAGAAGUCAGGAGGCCCCGCUUCGCGCUAACGCUUGCGAUGGUUGAAUUCCCCUCCUCACGCCAGCCUAGGAGAAGAAGUUCGUAGUCCCAGAGGAAGAGGAGUUGUACGCAUGUCAGAGAGGUUGCAGGCUGUUUUCAAUUUGUCAGUUUGUGGAUGAUGGAAUUGACUUAAAUCGAACUAAAUUGGAAUGUGAAUCUGCAUGUACAGAAGCAUAUUCCCAAUCUGAUGAGCAAUAUGCUUGCCAUCUUGGUUGCCAGAAUCAGCUGCCAUUCGCUGAACUGAGACAAGAACAACUUAUGUCCCUGAUGCCAAAAAUGCACCUACUCUUUCCUCUAACUCUGGUGAGGUCAUUCUGGAGUGACAUGAUGGACUCCGCACAGAGCUUCAUAACCUCUUCAUGGACUUUUUAUCUUCAAGCCGAUGACGGAAAAAUAGUUAUAUUCCAGUCUAAGCCAGAAAUCCAGUACGCACCACAUUUGGAGCAGGAGCCUACAAAUUUGAGAGAAUCAUCUCUAAGCAAAAUGUCCUCAGAUCUGCAAAUGAGAAAUUCACAAGCGCACAGGAAUUUUCUUGAAGAUGGAGAAAGUGAUGGCUUUUUAAGAUGCCUCUCUCUUAACUCUGGGUGGAUUUUAACUACAACUCUUGUCCUCUCGGUGAUGGUAUUGCUUUGGAUUUGUUGUGCAACUGUUGCUACAGCUGUGGAGCAGUAUGUUCCCUCUGAGAAGCUGAGUAUCUAUGGUGACUUGGAGUUUAUGAAUGAACAAAAGCUAAACAGAUAUCCAGCUUCUUCUCUUGUGGUUGUUAGAUCUAAAACUGAAGAUCAUGAAGAAGCAGGGCCUCUACCUACAAAAGUGAAUCUUGCUCAUUCUGAAAUUUAAGCAUUUUUCUUUUAAAAGACAAGUGUAAUAGACAUCUAAAAUUCCACUCCUCAUAGAGCUUUUAAAAUGGUUUCAUUGGAUAUAGGCCUUAAGAAAUCACUAUAAAAUGCAAAUAAAGUUACUCAAAUCUGUGAAGACUGUAUUUGCUAUAACUUUAUUGGUAUUGUUUUUGUAGUAAUUUAAGAGGUGGAUGUUUGGGAUUGUAUUAUUAUUUUACUAAUAUCUGUAGCUAUUUUGUUUUUUGCUUUGGUUAUUGUUUUUUUCCCUUUUCUUAGCUAUGAGCUGAUCAUUGCUCCUUCUCACCUCCUGCCAUGAUACUGUCAGUUACCUUAGUUAACAAGCUGAAUAUUUAGUAGAAAUGAUGCUUCUGCUCAGGAAUGGCCCACAAAUCUGUAAUUUGAAAUUUAGCAGGAAAUGACCUUUAAUGACACUACAUUUUCAGGAACUGAAAUCAUUAAAAUUUUAUUUGAAUAAUUAUGUGCUGAAAUUUGAGUAUCUGAUUUUUCUAGACCUUCCCUCCUAUUCCUGCCCAACCUAGAUAAGAAUUAUGAAAUGUUCUGUGUUUAUUGCUAUUGCUUUAUAAUGUGAUGGUCAGGGACCAUUUUGAUGCAAAACUGAUCUCUCAGCAGUACAUUUGAUGUUAUUUUGCACAGGCUAUAGGUUUUUGUUUGAUGAGUGUUUCCAAAGAACUAUUUUUCUCUGUUAGAUAGCAUAUCAAGUAUAAGGUAAACAUAUUUUCAGAGAAAACUUCAUUUUAACACUAAAAAUUAGACUCUUGUGAUACAGAAUUAAGUAUAAAUUUUACUUGGCAAAAACUCGUUUUAUUUUUACCUGCAAUAAUACAGAGCUUAAUAUUAGAAUGAUAUCAGGUCAUAAUAAUAAUACACCAGAAUCUUUUGAGAUGGAAUUUUGCUCUUGUUGCUGAGGCUGGAGUGCAAUGGUAUGAUCUUGGCUCACUACAACCUCCACCUCUGAGGUUCAAGCGAUUCUCCUGCCUCAGCCUCCCGAGUAGCUGGGAUUACAGGCAUGCGCCACCACACCUGGAUAAUUUUGUAUUUUUAGUAGAGACGGGGUUUCACCAGGUUGGCCAGGCUGGUCUCGAACUCCUGACCUCAGGUGAUCCACCCACUUAGGCCUUCCAAAGUGCUGGGAUUACAGGCGUGAGUGACUGUGCCCAGCCUACACCAGAAUUCUAAUAUGAUUCACUGUUAUUAUGCCAUAAAAUAUUAAAAACUUUGUAAAACAAUACUUUCCUCAGUCACAGGGGCAUUGCUGACAACUGCAUCAGUGCUGUUUGACUAAAGAAUAAGUUAGUCACUCCUCCUAUGGCCUAGUCUUUAGCCUUCCUGAGUCCAAAUGAAAAGCAGUUAACAGCUAAUCAAGGAAGACUUUGGUCACAAAGUGUAGGUUUUUAUUUUUAGUUUGUCUAGAUUUGGAUGAUAGAAAGUUGUGAACACAUCCAGAUGGGGAAGAAAGGAGGAAUUAGCCGUCAUUGUCAAGCAGUCAUUGUUUCUUUCUUCUUUUUGUUAGAAAACAUGGGAUAAAACGUGGGGACUCAGCCAGGCACAGUGGCUCACGCCUGUAAUCCCAGCACUUUGGGAGGCCAAAGCAGGAGGAUCACUUGAGGUCAGGAGUUCGAGACCAACCUGGGCAACAUAGCAAGACCCUCUCUGUACAAAAAAAUACAAACAAACAUGGGGACUAUAUAAAACAUGGGUAGUGGAUAGGAGUUACCAUUAAAAAAAAAUAAAAAGCCCUGUUGUUUCGUCUCCCAUCAUUAGUGCAUACUUAGUUUCCUUAGUCAGGCACAGGUUUAAUUGUAAUGCAUCCAAUGAAGCAAACAGAGAAACACAAAAUGCUGCUGUCUCACAGGAAUCAAAGAGCCCACUGUUAGAAAAGACCCUCCCUUAUAAAAACAAAACAAAGAAUUAUCUAGAUCACUUGGGGCCAGGAGUUCAACACCAUCCUGGGCAAUAUAAUGAGAAUCCCAUCUUUUUUUUUUUUUUUAAAGCAACUGUACAGUUGUCCUAUAUUCUCCACCUUCCCUUGGUUUCAUUUCUCUUCGCUUCCUGAAUGAGAAGUGCCUGAGAUACCUUCAUUUCUCUUGAAAGUAUUGAUCCAAGUUUAGACAAAUAUCUCCCCUCUUGUUGAGAGAAUUCCUUAUAUGUGAAAAUACCAAGACAUUCUUGAUAUUUAGCAGGCACUCAAAUAUUUGUCUCCUCUUUUUUAGCAUAAUUAAGCCAGACUGAUGUUUGCAUUUGAGUAUCAUCAGCAUGAGUAACCAUUUUAAUCUCUCUUCCCUUAACUACUUGUUCUACACUAGAGUCUAGGGUCAGGGUACGUACAGUGAUAAAGAUUGAGAUAAUGGGAAAUAUAGUCUUCUGUUUGGGAAGCUGGAUUGUAGUGUUGAUUUUCUGACUCCUUGUGGUAAUUAAAUUCUGAAGCACAGAAUCUACUUUUGAGAAGAAAUAUUUUACUUUUGAAAAAAAAUCCCCAAAAUAUAUACAGCAUAAAAAUGUUUCCGAUCUUGAAAAUCCCAACCAAAGCAACAAAACUGAGCUUCCAAGCCCCUUCUCCUAAAGUAACAGUUUUGCCCUUCUUGGAUGUGCCUAACUUUACUUAGCUCCUUGUUUCCAUAAAACAGUCAUAAUCUUAUUUCCUACCACACAGAAAGCAUCUUGAGAAUCUGGUCUUGGUCCUAGGCAAAUUCUCAAGACCGUUGGGUCUCUGGUUCAAACCUCCCAGACUUCUAAGGUCUUUCUUGGCUCAGGUCCCUCAUCUAAGAGACAUGCUAAUUCAGGCAAUUACAAAAGCAGUACUAAUCACCAUAAUGAAUGAUCUGGGCCUAGGUUCCAAGUUUUCUCACAAAACUUCAUGGGCACCUUUCAUUUGUGAUAUGUUUUGUAGUAAAUCAGAAAUUACUAGAUGAUCUGGUCAAUCUUAUCUCAGAAAUCCCUGUGGUGCAUCAUGAGGCAAUCUGAGCUGCUGAUCAGCAGAAAACCCUGCACUGUCUGAGCUUAUCUUCCAGCCAAAGGCAAACAAUUUACCCUUUGUUAUUAGUCUGUCUGGAUUUGUCUUAGAUAAAUGAGCCAUUUUUGUUACAAGUUUUUUAAAGAUAUACAGUAGUUCCAUUAUAAUUUUUGUGGACUCAAAUAUCAAGUCCACAUGUAGGGAAUCAUUGACAGAGAUUUCCAGUUACUGUCACCACCACACCAAGGCAGUAAUUUUGCUCAGUUCUGCCUUUAUAGAUCCACAAUUUAACCAUUCAACAACCACCUGAGAUCCUGAGUGGCAGGCCCUAUGCUAAAUGCUAGGACCACAGUAAGACCCAGUGCCUGACCCCAAUUGCUGAGACUCUGAAGGAGACUAUUAUUAAUGUGAUAAGUGCUAUGACCAAGCACAGAGCACAUAGGAGGAGCUGUAUGCAUUAUGGGAGCACACAGGAGGACUUCUGGGAGAAAGUGAUAGCCAAGCUUAAACCUGGAGAAAAAGGGAACGCCAAACACAAUAUAGAGAGCAGUGUACCAGACAGUGGGGACACUGUGCUCAAAGACCUAGAGGCCAGAGGGUGAGGCACUGCAGAUUGUUGAGUAGGCCGAGAUAGAGCAUACAAAAGCAUAACAAAAGAUGGGGCUAGGCAGACCAGGUAAUAAACCUGCACUUUAAACCUGCACUUGAUCCUGAGCACAGUAGAGAGCCACUGAAAGAUUUUAAGCAAGAGAGUGCCAUACAGUGUUGGAAUGAUUCACUCGGACAGCAAUGUGGAAGAUAGACCAGAAAGGGCAAGUCCAGAGGCCAACAAUAAUCUUAGCCUCAGAGUUCUUUUUUUAAUACCCAAGAAUACUAUUUCAUUUUACUUAUAUUUUUAAACUUUUCUCUAUAACGCUCUCUCUGCUCCCCCACAUUGUUGUCUGGAUGGUAAACCUAGGACUGGUCUCUGAGUCCUGGUCACAGCCUGGCAACAGAAUGUUUGAGCAAACUGGGAAGGCUGCCCCAUGGAUCCCUGGUUUCUUAUCACCAUCCUCUUAAUUCUACGUUUGCCAACCAGUCUCUAGGAAGCCAGCGUGCUCUUGCGCCCCUCCCACCAGGUUUCCAGUUGCUAAGCGUGUCAUGUUUGCAUUUGGGUAUCAUCUGCAUGAGUGACCAUUUUAAUCUCUCUUUCCUUGACUACUUGUUCUACACUAGAGUCUAGGGUGGGGGUGAGUACAGUGGUAAAGACAGGGAUAGCGGGAAAUUUAGUCUUCUGUUUAGGAAGCUGGAUGGUAGUGUGGAUUUUCUAACUCCUUGUGGUAAUUAAAUUCUGGAGCACAGUUUUUAGACCUUUUCUGAAAUCUGUUACUGUUGAAGUCAGCUUCAUAUAUUUCACUUUUUUUUUUUUUGAGACAGAGUCUCACACUGUUACUCAGGCUGGAGUGCACUGGUACAAUCUUGACUCACUGCAACCUCCACAGCUCCCAGGUUCAAGCGAUUCUCGUGCCUCAGCCUCCCAAGUAGCUGGUACUACAGGCGCGUGCCACCAUGCUUGGCUAAUUUUUGUAUUUCUAGUAAAGAUGGGGUUUUGCCAUGUUGCCCAGGCUGGUCUCGAACUCCUGGCCUCAGGUAAUCUGCCCGCCUCAGCCUCCCAAAGUGUUUGGAUUGCAGGCAUGAGCCACUGCACCCACCCUAUUUCACUAUUAAGUACUCUCUUCCUGUGAUAUUAAUGACUUAUUUGUUUCAAACUUUUUUGUGCCAUUGAGCUUUUUAGUGAUCCAGUGAAGCCUGUGGACCCCCUCUCAUAGUAAUGUUUUCAAAGCAUAAAACUAAAUAUAAAGGAUCGCAAAGGAAACUGAUCAUGUUAAAAUAAAGUUGAUAUUUUCAAAGUUUUAUGAUCCAGUAACAUACAUAUUCUGUUAACACAAAAUAAGACUGCAUGGUGGUUCUAAAAUUACUAUAAUUCAAAUUCAUAUCUUGAAAUAUCUAACAACUGUAAUAUAUCUAAAUGUCUCAUUUCUAUUGGUGACAAAGUCACAGGUACUCUGAUCCUACUGUGGACUGUUUCCUAUAUUCGUAAUUGAAGGAAAUGUUAUAUUUCAGUUAGAAGUUGGUGAAAAGAAAGAUUUAAAAUUUUUCCCAUCCAAGUUCACCAGACCCCUGGUUUAGAGGUUGUCUUAAUUUUACUUUUGUCAUUUUAAGAGUAAAUUAUUUUGUUUUCUUGUUCAAUUCUCAAUUAUUUGGGCUUAUUUUACUGCCUCUUGCAUGCUUUUUUAUGCUUGAAUGGUUUUUGCAGUGUUAGAACAGUAAUAAUUGAAGACUUGGGUGGAAAAAAAUCAGCACCUGAUUGAAAAUGAAAGGUUUCAACAAAAGCUCUUGAUAAUGUUACCUCCAGGUGUACCAUCAUGCCACCAUUAUUGGUGCUACAAAUCUGUUAAUUUAUUUAUGCUUAAGUAUGUAAACUUUAAUAAAACUUGGAUCAUCUGCAUUAAAAAAUAA